AUUUUCUUCCGGUGGCUGGUCUCCGGCGGCCCCGUCCCCGACUGGGCCCCGUGCCCCCCCGCCCCCGCGGCCCCCCGCCGCCGGGCCAGCCGCCACCAUGAAGAAAUUCUUUCAGGAGUUCAAGGCCGACAUCAAGUUCAAGAGCGCGGGACCCGGUCAGAAGCUCAAAGAGUCCGUGGGGGAAAAGGCCCACAAAGAGAAGCCCAACCAGCCAGCCCCCAGGCCGCCCCGCCAGGGACCCACCAAUGAGGCACAGAUGGCAGCCGCUGCCGCCCUAGCCCGGCUGGAGCAGAAGCAGUCCCGGGCCUGGGGCCCCACAUCGCAGGACACCAUCCGAAACCAGGUGAGAAAGGAACUUCAAGCCGAAGCCACCGUCAGCGGGAGCCCCGAGGCCCCAGGGACCAACGUGGUAUCUGAGCCCAGAGAGGAAGGCUCUGCCCACCUGGCUGUGCCUGGCGUGUACUUCACCUGUCCGCUCACUGGGGCCACCCUGAGGAAGGACCAGCGGGACGCCUGCAUCAAGGAGGCCAUUCUCUUGCACUUCUCCACCGACCCAGUGGCCGCCUCCAUCAUGAAGAUCUACACGUUCAACAAAGACCAGGACCGGGUGAAGCUGGGUGUGGACACCAUUGCCAAGUACCUGGACAACAUCCACCUGCACCCCGAGGAGGAGAAGUACCGGAAGAUCAAGCUGCAGAACAAGGUGUUUCAGGAGCGCAUUAACUGCCUGGAAGGGACCCACGAGUUUUUUGAGGCCAUUGGGUUCCAGAAGGUGUUGCUUCCCGCCCAGGAUCAGGAGGACCCCGAGGAGUUCUACGUGCUGAGCGAGACCACCUUGGCCCAGCCCCAGAGCCUGGAGAGGCACAAGGAACAGCUGCUGGCUGCGGAGCCCGUGCGCGCCAAGCUGGACAGGCAGCGCCGCGUCUUCCAGCCCUCGCCCCUGGCCUCGCAGUUCGAACUGCCUGGGGACUUCUUCAACCUCACAGCAGAGGAGAUCAAGCGGGAGCAGAGGCUCAGGUCCGAGGCGGUGGAGCGGCUGAGCGUGCUGCGGACCAAGGCCAUGCGGGAGAAGGAGGAGCAGCGGGGGCUGCGCAAGUACAACUACACGCUGCUGCGCGUGCGCCUCCCCGAUGGCUGCCUCCUGCAGGGCACUUUCUACGCUCGGGAGCGGCUGGGGGCGGUGUACGGGUUCGUCCGGGAGGCCCUGCAGAGCGACUGGCUGCCUUUUGAGCUGCUGGCCUCGGGAGGGCAGAAGCUGUCCGAGGACGAGAACCUGGCCUUGAACGAGUGCGGGCUGGUGCCCUCUGCCCUCCUGACCUUCUCGUGGGACAUGGCUGUGCUGGAGGACAUCAAGGCCGCGGGGGCCGAGCCGGACUCCAUCCUGAAACCCGAGCUCCUGUCAGCCAUCGAGAAGCUCUUGUGAAAUAAAAGCAGGGUUGGCCUCAGCCCUGUGGGUCUGUCUCAUGCUCUCCCUGUUCCUCUCCCCGCCACCCCAGGGCCUCCAAGCCACCUCUGGAAAUACUUGGCUCUGCCCCAUGGGCACGGGAGGGGCGCCAGCCGUGGAGCUGUGGAAUUGGGCCCCGUGGCAGAGCCCCCAUCCCUUGGGGGCUGUGGGGAUGCGCCCAAGCCCCCGAGGGAGAGGCCUGGGGACACCAACAAAUCUAAGCCCUCCCUAGCUGCUUGGUAACUGUGUCAUGAAGCUGCCGGACAGACACACGUGGCAUCUCCCUGGGCAGGAGAGCAGGCCUGCAGCAUGGGUCCUGUUCCCGUGUGCCGUGGGUGGCAGUGGCUGCACCUGGCACUAGGGCUGCUCUGUGGAUGUGGGUGACAACGGCAGGAGGGGAUGCUGGCCUUCCUGCACAUAGACCUGCAGUUAGUAAAUCAUAAGCCCAAAUAAACAGGUUGUUUGAAUAUA